AGCCGGGUCCACUGCCGGGUGGAGGGGCAAGGCGAGUGUGUGUCCUUAUCCUAGCAAUUGGGGCGCGGGCCUGUGAGCCAGUUGGAGUUGCGGCGGCGGGAACGAUUGGGCUGAGCAGAGGACGACAUGUUGCUUUUCGUGGAGCAUUUAUGGGGUUAAGUGGCAUGGGAUUUCUGUUUCUGAUAGUAAAUAGUGAGAAUCAGAGCGUCUACUGCACCUUUCAGAUGACCGGGUGCCGUGGCUCAACACCUAUAAUCCCAGCACUUGGGAUGGGAGGCUAAGCAGGUAGCAUCUAAAGGAACUGGUUUAAAUCCUAAUGCCAAAGUAUGGCAAGAAAUUGCUCCUGGAAAUACUGAUGCCACCCCAGUAACUCAUGGAACUGAAAGCUCUUGGCAUGAAAUAGCAGCUACAUCAGGUGCUCAUCCUGAGGGUAAUGCAGAGCUCUCAGAAGAUAUAUGUAAAGAAUAUGAAGUAAUGUAUUCUUCAUCUUGUGAAACCACAAGAAAUACUACAGGCAUUGAAGAAUCAACUGAUGGGAUGAUUUUAGGACCAGAAGAUCUGAGUUACCAAAUAUAUGAUGUUUCCGGAGAAAGCAAUUCAGCAGUUUCUACAGAAGACCUAAAAGAAUGUCUGAAGAAACAAUUAGAAUUCUGUUUUUCACGAGAAAAUUUGUCAAAGGAUCUUUACUUGAUAUCUCAAAUGGAUAGUGAUCAGUUCAUCCCAAUUUGGACAGUUGCCAACAUGGAAGAAAUAAAAAAGUUGACUACAGACCCUGAUCUAAUUCUUGAAGUGUUAAGAUCUUCUCCCAUGGUACAAGUUGAUGAGAAGGGUGAGAAAGUGAGACCAAGUCAUAAGCGUUGUAUUGUAAUUCUUAGAGAGAUUCCUGAAACAACACCAAUAGAGGAAGUGAAAGGUUUGUUCAAAAGUGAAAACUGCCCCAAAGUGAUAAGCUGUGAGUUUGCACACAAUAGCAACUGGUAUAUCACUUUCCAGUCAGACACAGAUGCACAACAGGCUUUUAAAUACUUAAGAGAAGAAGUUAAAACAUUUCAGGGCAAGCCAAUUAUGGCAAGGAUAAAAGCCAUCAAUACAUUUUUUGCUAAGAAUGGUUAUCGAUUAAUGGAUUCUAGUAUCUAUAGUCACCCCAUUCAAACUCAAGCACAGUAUGCCUCCCCAGUCUUUAUGCAGCCUGUAUAUAAUCCUCACCAACAGUACUCGGUCUAUAGUAUUGUGCCUCAGUCUUGGUCUCCAAAUCCUACACCUUACUUUGAAACACCACUGGCUCCCUUUCCCAAUGGUAGUUUUGUGAAUGGCUUUAAUUCGCCAGGAUCUUAUAAAACAAAUGCUGCUGCUAUGAAUAUGGGUCGACCAUUCCAAAAAAAUCGUGUGAAGCCUCAGUUUAGGUCAUCUGGUGGUUCAGAACACUCAACAGAGGGCUCUGUAUCCUUGGGGGAUGGACAGUUGAACAGAUAUAGUUCAAGAAACUUUCCAGCUGAACGGCAUAACCCCACAGUAACUGGGCAUCAGGAGCAAACUUACCUUCAGAAGGAGACUUCCACUUUGCAGGUGGAACAGAAUGGGGACUAUGGUAGGGGCAGGAGAACUCUCUUCAGAGGUCGAAGACGACGAGAAGAUGACAGGAUCUCAAGACCUCAUCCUUCAACAGCUGAAUCAAAGGCUCCAACACCAAAGUUUGACUUAUUAGCCUCAAAUUUUCCACCUUUACCUGGAAGUUCAUCAAGAAUGCCAGGUGAACUCGUUUUGGAGAAUAGGAUGUCUGAUGUUGUUAAAGGUGUCUACAAAGAAAAGGAUAAUGAAGAGUUGACAAUUAGUUGCCCAGUGCCUGCAGAUGAGCAGACAGAAUGCACUUCUGCCCAGCAACUCAAUAUGAGUACCAGUUCUCCAUGUGCUGCUGAGCUUACUGCAUUAAGCACAACUCAGCAAGAAAAGGAUCUAAUAGAAGAUUCCUCUGUUCAGAAGGAUGGUCUCAAUCAGACAACUAUACCAGUUUCUCCUCCAAGUACUACAAAGCCAUCGAGGGCAAGUACUGCUUCACCAUGUAAUAAUAACAUAAAUGCAGCUACAGCUGUGGCUCUACAGGAACCCCGAAAGUUAAGUUAUGCUGAAGUGUGCCAGAAGCCCCCUAAAGAGCCAUCUUCAGUUCUUGUGCAGCCACUACGGGAACUUCGCUCCAAUGUGGUGUCUCCCACCAAAAAUGAAGACAAUGGAGCUCCUGAGAACUCCGUUGAGAAACCACAUGAGAAGCCAGAAGCAAGGGCUAGUAAGGAUUAUUCUGGCUUCCGAGGCAAUAUAAUCCCCAGGGGAGCAGCAGGAAAAAUCAGGGAACAGAGACGCCAGUUUAGCCAUAGGGCUAUACCUCAGGGAGUGACUCGACGUAAUGGCAAAGAGCAAUAUGUGCCACCCAGAUCACCAAAGUAAAAAACAACAAAACUAUUCAAAAACUUCACUCUCUUCCCAUUAAACUUGAACUGUGGCUAUAUUGAACUGUUUUGGAGGGGAGGGGGUAGCCAGGAAGGAAACAAGAGAAAGUACGUCCAUUUCAUUAUGGAUUUUGGAGUUGUGAGUGAUAGGAUCCCAAAAUUCAUCUCUAAUGUGGUUUUUAAAUGCUGGAGGAUUCCAAUCAAUAUAAAUAUAUAUAUAUAUAUACACACACAUAUAUAAAAAGUAUAAUUUUUCUAUUUUUGUUUUUGGUUUUAAUUUGCAGAGAUUUGCUGCCAGGAAUCAAUUUUGAGGGUUCAGAUUUAGCUUGGAAGAAAAAAAAGAAACAUACAUCCUUCAGUAUAGGAGAUGAGGGAAUGAGAGAAAAUAUUUUUUGAAGAAGCAUUUCUGUAAAAUUAGAAAUUACUUUUUUUAAUCUAUUUAAAGUUUGGCUUGAAGAAUGCCAUCUCUGACUAUAUGGCCUUGUAUUGCAAAGCGGAUCAGUGGCUGGGGUGCCUGUUGUGGGUGUGAGUGUGUACAAGAGCGAUUGAAGCCAAAUCUGUUGUCAUGUUAGUAAAUGAUUUGAAAACUGAAUGUAAUACUUGAGUAGAUUUUUUUUUCUAGUUUGAAAUUUAGUCUGUCUUUUUGACCUUACUAAUAUUUCAUUUAACAAGUUGUAAAACUCUGAUUGUACUUAGAGAUGUGACUACCAAUCAGUUUGAUACUCAAGGAAAGGGGGUUAUUCAAGAAAUUGAAAAUUUCAUCUUGGACCUCAGUGCAUAGGUCAAAUGGAUUUCAGAGGUUUAAACUUCCCUGUGAUUCCCCCGAAUACCCCCAAAAUGAGAAACAAAAUUUUUUUUCUUACUCCAUUUGUUACUCUCUGUUCUUUGACUGCCCACCCACAGAAAAGCAAAAUAACCAACUACCUACUCAAUUGUGUGUUUGUAAUUGCUUUGAGCAGUCUAGUCAAAUCAUAUAAAUUGUUCUAAAUUUCAGAAUUGAACAUUGAAGUAUUAACUCUUCUGUUCACACAUUUAGAAUUUUAGCUCCCAAGAUGGUAGGGCAGACUGACCGUACAGUAAUUUAUUUGUCGUUAGUGUUAAAGAUUAAGCAUAGUAACUGACUCUUAAGUGUUAAAUAAUGUAGAAGUAAAAAAAUUUUUUUUAAAGGCUUAAUUUGGGAGGGGGGACUUAUUUCUGUUUACAGUGUAUUACCUUCCUUCCCUCCUCUUCUCCCCCCACACCCAACAAAAUACAGUUUGGAAUUCACUGAAACAGUACCAGCAAGUCAUGAGAUUUUUUAGUAAAGAUGAGAAAGAUGGUUGAAGAAAAUUAGUGCAUAAUUUCUCAGUGAAUAAAGUUGUAGCUCUCAUAUACUAAAUAGACAAGUUUACAUGCUGUUAUUUAGAAAAUGACUAAAAUAUUAAAAACCGUGUUGUGUUAAUCUGUUUUAAGUCAUACCAUGUUCAGAGUUCUAUGUAAGGUGGGUUUUAUUUUUCUUUUAAGGGAUAGUUUGUAAUAGUAAGAACUGUCCCAUAUGUUAGUAAAUUACAUAUGUACAAAUUGAAACUGUAAAUUGUGAACACUGGAAAGCACCAUUGUGACAUAGAGUAAACAUCUUAGUAAUAUAUUAAAGUGAAUGUAAAUGGUGGUUAAAAUUACAUUACUGUGAAAUUCAUCUUCCAACUCUAAGUUAAGCUUUGGAGAUACAUGUUAGUGGUUAACUGUUAAGAGCUUUGAAAACACUGCACAUAUCUGUACAAGCCAGAAUUACUAUUUCUUUGACUUAUUAUUAGCUUGGCAGUUGCUUUUGAUUUGAUUGUUUUAUGACAUGGUAUACUACUAUAUUUACUCAGUUUGAAACUAUUCAUUUCUACACACUAUUUUUAAAAAUUGCCUACUAGGUGAAACAUAACAAUAAAACUACCUGUGCUGAAAUUUGGGGGAAGUUUAGGUCCUUUAAAAAAACAUAUUAAUCAUUGACUACAUCUAUGAUAAAAGUGCUUAUUUUGGUUUACUAAGAUAAUGCAGUUGGUGGAAAUGAUAAACGUUUUAAGUGUUAACAUCCUUUGAAUGCGUUGGAUUUCAGAGAAUAAACAUUUUGUAAAAAUCACUUGGUAAGGAUUAUAAACUUAAUUACUGCACUUAAAAUGAAACAUUACUUUUUUUAAACAAUGUGUCACAAAUGUAGGUCUGUAUUACUUGUAUGCUUGUGUGACUUACUGUUAGUCCAGCUCUAAAAAUUUAAAGGUUGUAAUUGAAAUACAAGAAAAGAGCCUUCUUUUAGAAGAAAGCAAGUAUAUUUUUGCUUUUACUUCAAAUGUUAUUUAAAGUAGAAAUUUAAUUUGUAGAUAUAACCUUUAAAAAUUUUCUCAUUAAGACAAUGUUUUUAAUUUAAUUUGCCUCAUUACAUCUAAUAGUUCCCAUUUGAUGGCAUGUAUAGGGAAGAGUGAGAGAGUGUGUGUGUGUGUAUGUGUGUGUAAUAUUUAUAUAUAUUCACAGUAUGUAUUUAGCAUUUAUUUUAUUACAGCAGAUUUAAAGUUUGUAUCUAAAUAAUGCCUAUGAGUUGUGUGAAGCUCUUGGCUUUUUUCCAACGUUACUUUGUAACUAAUGAGGGUGGAUGUUCAUUGUAGUUUAUUUAUUUGGUUCUUUAGAUGGAGGAAUUUAAAAAAUCAAAUUUUUCUCUUCACCUUUAUGACUUGACAUUUCCUUGAUCUGUUGGAGGCUAAAAGUAGGUAUAAAUGAUAUUGAAUGUUGGGUAUAGUGAUACUCUGCCAUAGUUCUUACUGCAUGAAGAGAACAAGAGUCACACAAGUUCACCACUUUGCACUUCAUAGAGAAGGUACAUAGAGACAUUGCAAAACCUGUCUCCAUUUGCUAUCCUGAUAAUUAAGGUUUUCAUAAUACCUAGGGCCUGUCUCUGAGUAAUUUUAAUUUUGCCAAAUACACUGACAUUUAAAAUAGUGAUCCAUCUAAAUUUUUUUCAGCUGGGUUUUGAGGAAUAUAAGAGCUUUCAAUGAUAAAGGUUUGUUGUAGUUGUCUUAUGUGCUGAAUUUGCAGAUGAUCAGAUGCUGUGCAGAAUUCUGAUUUAUUUUUGUUUCCUAAAAUUAAGAUAGCUUGAAUAUUAUUUCACAUUCCUUUUUCUUUUUUAAAUAAACAGGUUUGCUUUGGAAAGGCUUAAUGAUGGAAUGUUAGCAUCUUCACUAGGGUAAAGAAGAACAAAAAGAAUGUUGCUGGAACGUAAAAUAGUAUUUAAAAGUUAAUGAACACUUCUCUAGUUUUCUUAGUUAUGGCCUUAAUAAUUAGUCUCUUGGCUUAAAUGUCCACUGGUUUUACUUUGACACAGUUGAACAACACUGGGGUUAAGUCUCUGGUAUUUAGGCUGGCAAUAUAUAUAUUAACCAUAUUUUAAAAGUACCAAUUUUGUUUUUACAGAAAAGAUAAAACUCAAAAGAGAACAGUGUAUUCCUUCUGAGGGGCUUUUAUAAAUUAUUAACUAUAAUAUAUGAUGGAUUUUUUCCUAAUUUUUUAUAUUUCCUUACAAUUUUGGUGGCCAUUAAUUUAACUUUAGGCUUUUGGGCAUAUGCUAGUCUGAGCUUCCGAAAAGAUACAUAUAUGUUUCCCUUUUCAUUAGCUGAAUGAGGAUAUUUUAAGAAGUUGAAAGAGAAUUUAUUUUCAAGUUGUGAGUAAAUCCUCCUUUGAAAUUCACCUGAUUAUUAGAUAACUUAAAGUUUAUUUUUAAAAGCUGACAACUUUUUAUGAAUCUUCGAGUUGACAGUUCCUAAAAGCGUAACUCAGAUAUUAAUGGGCUGUGUAUUAAAUGGUUUUAUUUUCAGUUUUGCAGCACAGAACACUGUUGAAAUAUCCAUAUCAACUUGAUUUUUUUAACCUAAUUCAGGUGUCCUUUGCAUCUCUUAAAUGUUGGGGGUGGGGGUCAGAGCCAGUUAUCCGGCUUCUGUUUUGUCGAUUGCUUAGAUUUGUUCCUGUUGUCAAAACUGUUACCCCCAAAAUUGGUGUGACACAUGCUCAUGCAUAAAAUGUUAAAAUGAGUACAUCCUUGUAUUUGUAUUUGUUUUCAACAUCGCCAAGGUGCUAUGGGAAAUUAACAAAAUUAGAAAAAAAAUAAAAUUAUUAAAAAGCA